CUUAGUGUACCUAGUCUACUUAAUCAACACUUAGUGUAUUUAGUGUUUCAGCUUAGUGUAGAGAGGCUUCUUUCUUCCUUUUCUGGAGGAGUCAGUGGUUAGAGACGAUUUCCGUGGUUAGAGCGUACUUGGUCUUUAGAAGACGACUUUGGUGUCCAUUGCCAACCCCAUCAGAGAUCGCAGGCCUUUUCCCCUCAGUCCCAGCUCAUCAGCAAAGGUCUGGGUGGCUGUCUCCAGAGGAGACUGAACGAGGUUGUCAAAGCGGCUGGAUCAAAAGUGUUGCCAUGUCGGAUGGAGUGGUGUCCACGAUGAACCUGAGCAUGGAGAUUUCUCCCUCUGCGCUGAGGAUCUCACUGUGCACCUCCAGCCCUGGGUCCUGGUGGGCUCUGGUGGCCACUGGAGUCUUUGGAACUGCCUCCCUCUGGCUCUGCUGGGGUUGGAUUCGGGCAUCGAUGUCACACCCAGCAGGAACAACUGGGGCCACUGGAGGAUUCCCAAGGACACAGGUUGUCCUUUUCAUGCAGGAAGAAUCUGAAUCGUUUCCAUCCAGUUUCCCCGGCAUGCAGCAGAAUACAACACAAGGGGCUGCGGUCUUCUCUGACUCUUAAGGCCCUUGGAAGAUCCUGUUCUGCCAAAAUCAGGGUGAUUUGGGCAAGCAUCCUUAGGGCUCUGGACCUUAGUUUCUUUCCCUGGUUGAUUGAUUGACCAUAUAGGUGUCCUAACUCACAUAGUUGAAAAUCAGAUGUGGUGAAAGUGCAUUGAGACCAGAAACAAUGUUAUUGUCCUGAAAUGCAUGCCCAGAGAGCACUGAAUAAAUUUUUAAAACACCUGA